UAUUUCAGUGUGAGGUUUCAAAGGGUCAAACAUCUAAACUAAAGCAGCUGUAUCCUCAGCAUGUUCUAUGGUUUCUAUGAGAGCUGUAACUGAGAAAGCAGGAGAAAGCUGGGUCUCCCGCCAUCAGGCUGCUUGUCCUAAGGAGAUGUUCCAUGUGGUUACCUGUCAAUCAAGAAAUGAGACAAUCCAUAAAGAGGAACUGCUAUGAUUAGCUUCUUAUUGGAUUCCCAUCUUCCUCCAGGUAUCUGCAGACACCUGCAUGUUCUGAUUGGGACCUCAGUGGUCAUCUUCCUCUUCAUCCUCCUCCUCUUCUUUCUCCUUUAUCGCUGGUGCUCCAACAAAAAGAAUGCUGCUGUAAUGGACCAAGAGCCUGCGGGGGACAGAACAGUGAAUAGGCAGGACUCUGAUGAACAAGACCCUCAGGAGGUGACGUACGCACAGUUGGAUCACUGCGUUUUCAUACAGAGAAAAAUCAGUCGCCCUUCUCAGAGGCCCAAGACACCCCUAACAGAUACCAGCGUGUACACGGAACUUCCAAAUGCUGAGCCCAGAUCCAAAGUUGUCUCCUGCCCACGAGCACCACAGUCAGGUCUUGAGGGGGUUUUCUAGGGAGACAACAGCCCUGUCUCAAAACCAGGUUGCCAGAUCCAAUGAACCAGCAGCUGGAAUCUGAAGGCAUCAGUCUGCAUCUUAGGGGAUCGCUCUUCCUCACACCACGAAUCUGAACAUGCCUCUCUCUUGCUUACAAAUGCCUAAGGUCGCCACUGCCUGCUGCAGAGAAAACACACUCCUUUGCUUAGCCCACAAGUAUCUAUUUCACUUGACCCCUGCCCACCUCUCCAACCUAACUGGCUUACUUCCUAGUCCUACUUGAGGCUGCAAUCACACUGAGGAACUCACAAUUCCAAACAUACAAGAGGCUCCCUCUUAACACGGCACUUACACACUUGCUGUUCCACCUUCCCUCAUGCUGUUCCACCUCCCCUCAGACUAUCUUUCAGCCUUCUGUCAUCAGUAAAAUUUAUAAAUUUUUUUUAUAACUUCAGUGUAGCUCUCUCCUCUUCAAAUAAACAUGUCUGCCCUCA